CUCGUGUUCGGGAGGUUGGAUCUCAGACGUGUUUUGAGUUGGUCAUAGUGAAGGACACUAGGUGUCAAAUUCUAGCGAGAACAAUUUCCAGGAAGCCGUGUUCCGCUCUUGAGCGAGCACCCACUGGGCCUCAUGCAAGGUAGAAAGAGCCUGCGUACGUCACCCUCCCAUGAUGUGGUCAACAUGUAAACUGCAUGGGCAGGGCGCCAAAUAACAUCCUGUGCGCUGCUGAGCUGAGCUCGGUCGCGGCUGCCUGUCUGCUCCGGCAGCACCAUGUCGCUCUUGGUCGUCAGCAUGGCGUGUGUUGGGUUCUUCUUGCUGCAGGGGGCCUGGCCACAUGAGGGAGUCCACAGAAAACCUUCCCUCCUGGCCCACCCAGGUCGCCUGGUGAAAUCAGAAGAGACAGUCAUCCUGCAAUGUUGGUCAGAUGUCAUGUUUGAACACUUCCUUCUGCACAGAGAGGGGAUGUUUAACGACACUUUGCGCCUCAUUGGAGAACACCAUGAUGGGGUCUCCAAGGCCAACUUCUCCAUCAGUCGCAUGAAGCAAGACCUGGCAGGGACCUACAGAUGCUACGGUUCUGUUACUCACUCCCCCUAUCAGUUGUCAGCUCCCAGUGACCCUCUGGACAUCGUGAUCAUAGGUCUAUAUGAGAAACCUUCUCUCUCAGCCCAGCCGGGCCCCACGGUUCUGGCAGGAGAGAAUGUGACCUUGUCCUGCAGCUCCCGGAGCUCCUAUGACAUGUACCAUCUAUCCAGGGAAGGGGAGGCCCAUGAACGUAGGCUCCCUGCAGGGACCAAGGUCAACGGAACAUUCCAGGCCAACUUUCCUCUGGGCCCUGCCACCCAUGGAGGGACCUACAGAUGCUUCGGCUCUUUCCGUGACUCUCCAUACGAGUGGUCAAAGUCAAGUGACCCACUGCUUGUUUCUGUCACAGGAAACCCUUCAAAUAGUUGGCCUUCACCCACUGAACCAAGCUCCGAAACCGGUAACCCCAGACACCUACAUGUUCUGAUUGGGACCUCAGUGGUCAAAAUCCCUUUCACCAUCCUCCUCUUCUUUCUCCUUCAUCGCUGGUGCUCCGACAAAAAAAAUGCUGCUGUAAUGGACCAAGAGCCUGCAGGGAACAGAACAGUGAACAGCGAGGAUUCUGAUGAACAAGACCAUCAGGAGGUGUCAUACGCAUAAUUGGAUCACUGUGUUUUCACACAGAGAAAAAUCACUCGCCCUUCUGAGAGGCCCAAGACACCCCCAACAGAUACCAGCAUGUACAUAGAACUUCCAAAUGCUGAGCCCAGAUCCAAAGUUGUCUUCUGUCCACGAGCACCACAGUCAGGCCUUGAGGGGAUCUUCUAGGGAGA